ACUGCGAAGCCCAGCUGCGCGCGCCUUGGGAUUGACUGUCCACGCUCGCCCGGCUCGUCCGACGCGCCCUCCGCCAGCCGACAGACACAGCCGCACGCACUGCCGUGUUCUCCCUGCGGCUCGGACACAUAGUAUGACCAUUAGGUGUUUCGUCUCCCACCCAUUUUCUAUGGAAAACCAAGGGGAUCGGGCCAUGAUAGCCACUGGCAGCUUUGAAGAACGGGACACCUUUAGAGAAGCUUGAUCUUGGAGGCCUCACCGUGAGACCUUACAAAGCCGGCUGGGUCUUAUUCUUCUCUGGCCUUCACAACAUCCUGCAACCCAGCUCAAGGUCAGGAAUGUGACAGACUCAUGUCAUCAUAUCUCUGAUGCCCAGAGAAGGGAUACCAUUUGCCUGAGCCUUCUCAGUACUGUUUAAUCAGCCUGUGAGAACUUUCCUUGUGAAAGGCCCUGUCUGUGCCUGGGGCUGAUAAAACAGCAAGAACGAACUGAGGAGCUGGGCAGCAGUGCAAAGCAAAUACUACCAGCUUUGGUGCCUAUUCCGGCAGAGUUCCUCUAUCUCGUCUUGUUGCUGAUUAAAGGUGCCCCUGUCUCCAGUUUUUCUCCAUCUCCUGGGACGUAGCAGGAAAUCAGCAUCAUGGUUGGGUUCAAGGCCACAGAUGUGCCCCCUACUGCCACUGUGAAGUUUCUUGGGGCUGGCACAGCUGCCUGCAUCGCAGAUCUCAUCACCUUUCCUCUGGAUACUGCUAAAGUCCGGUUACAGAUCCAAGGAGAAAGUCAGGGGCCAGUGCGCGCUACAGCCAGCGCCCAGUACCGCGGUGUGAUGGGCACCAUUCUGACCAUGGUGCGUACUGAGGGCCCCCGAAGCCUCUACAAUGGGCUGGUUGCCGGCCUGCAGCGCCAAAUGAGCUUUGCCUCUGUCCGCAUCGGCCUGUAUGAUUCUGUCAAACAGUUCUACACCAAGGGCUCUGAGCAUGCCAGCAUUGGGAGCCGCCUCCUAGCAGGCAGCACCACAGGUGCCCUGGCUGUGGCUGUGGCCCAGCCCACGGAUGUGGUAAAGGUCCGAUUCCAAGCUCAGGCCCGGGCUGGAGGUGGUCGGAGAUACCAAAGCACCGUCAAUGCCUACAAGACCAUUGCCCGAGAGGAAGGGUUCCGGGGCCUCUGGAAAGGGACCUCUCCCAAUGUUGCUCGUAAUGCCAUUGUCAACUGUGCUGAGCUGGUGACCUAUGACCUCAUCAAGGAUGCCCUCCUGAAAGCCAACCUCAUGACAGAUGACCUCCCUUGCCACUUCACUUCUGCCUUUGGGGCAGGCUUCUGCACCACUGUCAUCGCCUCCCCUGUAGACGUGGUCAAGACGAGAUACAUGAACUCUGCCCUGGGCCAGUACAGUAGCGCUGGCCACUGUGCCCUUACCAUGCUCCAGAAGGAGGGGCCCCGAGCCUUCUACAAAGGGUUCAUGCCCUCCUUUCUCCGCUUGGGUUCCUGGAACGUGGUGAUGUUCGUCACCUAUGAGCAGCUGAAACGAGCCCUCAUGGCUGCCUGCACUUCCCGAGAGGCUCCCUUCUGAGCCUCUCCUGCUGCUGACCUGAUCACCUCUGGCUUUGUCUCUAGCCGGGCCAUGCUUUCCUUUUCUUCCUUCUUUCUCUUCCCUCCUUCCCUUCUCUCCUUCCCUCUUUCCCCACCUCUUCCUUCCGCUCCUUUACCUACCACCUUCCCUCUUUCUACAUUCUCAUCUACUCAUUGUCUCAGUGCUGGUGGAGUUGACAUUUGACAGUGUGGGAGGCCUCGUACCAGCCAGGAUCCCAAGCGUCCCGUCCCUUGGAAAGUUCAGCCAGAAUCUUCGUCCUGCCCCCGACAGCCCAGCCUAGCCCACUUGUCAUCCAUAAAGCAAGCUCAACCUUG